CCUCCUGUCUUGUCUCAGCGGCUGCCAACAGGUAAGGAAACCCAAGGCUUUUCACCCAAAUAUACUGCCUGCUGUCCAGAGGGCACACUUAGGAUCAUGAGCCAUCAGCUCCUCUGGGGCCAGCUAUAGGACAACAGAACUCUCACCAAAGGACCAGACACAGUGGGCACCAUGGGACAGUGUCGGUCAGCCAACGCAGAGGAUGCUCAGGAAUUCAGUGAUGUGGAGAGGGCCAUUGAGACCCUCAUCAAGAACUUUCACCAGUACUCCGUGGAGGGUGGGAAGGAGACGCUGACCCCUUCUGAGCUACGGGACCUGGUCACCCAGCAGCUGCCCCAUCUCAUGCCGAGCAACUGUGGCCUGGAAGAGAAAAUUGCCAACCUGGGCAGCUGCAAUGACUCUAAACUGGAGUUCAGGAGUUUCUGGGAGCUGAUUGGAGAAGCGGCCAAGAGUGUGAAGCUGGAGAGGCCUGUCCGGGGGCACUGAGAACUCCCUCUGGAAUUCUUGGGGGGUGUUGGGGAGAGACUGUGGGCCUGGAGAUAAAACUUGUCUCCUCUACCACCACCCUGUACCCUAGCCUGCACCUGUCCUCAUCUCUGCAAAGUUCAGCUUCCUUCCCCAGGUCUCUGUGCACUCUGUCUUGGAUGCUCUGGGGAGCUCAUGGGUGGAGGAGUCUCCACCAGAGGGAGGCUCAGGGGACUGGUUGGGCCAGGGAUGAAUAUUUGAGGGAUAAAAAUUGUGUAAGAGCCAAAGAAUUGGUAGUAGGGGGAGAACAGAGAGGAGCUGGGCUAUGGGAAAUGAUUUGAAUAAUGGAGCUGGGAAUAUGGCUGGAUAUCUGGUACUAAAAAAGGGUCUUUAAGAACCUACUUCCUAAUCUCUUCCCCAAUCCAAACCAUAGCUGUCUGUCCAGUGCUCUCUUCCUGCCUCCAGCUCUGCCCCAGGCUCCUCCUAGACUCUGUCCCUGGGCUAGGGCAGGGGAGGAGGGAGAGCAGGGUUGGGGGAGAGGCUGAGGAGAGUGUGACAUGUGGGGAGAGGACCAGCUGGGUGCUUGGGCAUUGACAGAAUGAUGGUUGUUUUGUAUCAUUUGAUUAAUAAAAAAAAAUGAAAAAAGUGAAA